AGACGCGGCGGCUCUCAGCUCGCGAGCGCAGCUGCGGCUGCGAGGGCCUCUCAGGCCGACACUCCCCCCGCGCCCCUCCCCCACCCGGCCGGGCUCCGGACCCGCCGCGCGCGAGCCCGCGGCCGCUUCCCCCGCGCCGAGCGAGGAGGCAGGCUGCGGCGGCGAGAGGCGGCUGCGCGGCCAUGGGCGCGCCAGUGUCGCCCUAGGGCGGGCGCACAGACCACAGCCGGAGCGGUGGUGGCAGCCUCCGCAGAAAGCCUUCCCGGGCGGCGGCGGCGGCGGCCCCUGGAGCAGCGCGGCCGGGAUGAGCGGGAGCUGCGCGGCGCCCGGCCCGGGCUCGGGCUCCUCCCCGGCCGCCUGCCGCUUCGCGCACUACUUCGUGCUGUGCGGGAUCGACGCGGACAGCGGGCUGGAGCCUGACGAGCUGGCGGAGAUACGGGGUCAACCUUCAUUCUUCUGCGUAAAGAUAUCCAGUUUUCCCAGCACCAUUGACUGAAGAGACUGUCCUUUCUCCAUUGUAUGUUCUCGGCACCUUUGUCUAAAUUUUGUACCAAUGGCUAGAAGCAGAUCGUCAUGGCAAGAGCCAAGGUGCUGCAAAUACGACUUCAGGCGAAAAUUUUGACCAGAGUCCUUUGAGAAGAACAUUCAAAUCCAAAGUUCUCGCCCACUAUCCUCAGAAUAUAGAAUGGAACCCUUUUGAUCAAGAUGCGGUGAACAUGUUGUGCAUGCCUAAAGGGCUAUCUUUCAGGACACAAACGGACAAUAAAGACCCCCAGUUUCACUCAUUUAUAAUUACCAGGGAAGAUGGUUCUCGCACCUAUGGUUUUGUUCUCACUUUUUAUGAAGAAGUUACAAGUAAGCAAAUCUGCACAGCAAUGCAGACACUUUACCAGAUGCACAACGCUGAGCAUUACAGCAGUGUGUAUGCUUCAUCUUCCUGCAGUAUGGACUCAUUGGCAAGUAGUCUUGAUGAAGGAGAUACAACUUCCCUUUUGAAACUCCAGCGAUACAACUCCUAUGAUAUUAGCAGAGACACCCUGUAUGUUUCAAAAAGUAUAUGCUUGAUCACACCGUUACCAUUCAUGCAGGCCUGCAAGAAAUUCCUUAUCCAGCUUUACAAGGCUGUUACCUCACAGCAGCCACCACCCUUGCCACUUGAAAGCUAUAUCCACAAUAUUCUUUAUGAAGUACCCCUUCCACCUCCAGGGAGGUCACUGAAAUUUUAUGGUGUUUAUGAACCUGUCAUCUGCCAGAGGCCUGGGCCCAGUGAACUCCCCCUCUCUGAUUACCCCCUUCGGGAGGCAUUUGAGCUCCUGGGAUUAGAGAACCUGGUGCAGGUGUUUACCUGUGUUCUUUUAGAGAUGCAAAUCCUUCUCUACUCACAAGAUUAUCAACGCCUGAUGACUGUGGCAGAAGGCAUCACCACACUUUUGUUCCCAUUUCAAUGGCAACAUGUUUAUGUGCCCAUUCUACCUGCUUCUCUGCUACAUUUUCUUGAUGCUCCUGUCCCUUAUCUGAUGGGCCUUCAGUCAAAAGAAGGAACUGACCGUUCUAAACUAGAACUUCCUCAAGAGGCUAAUUUGUGUUUUGUGGACAUUGACAACCAUUUUAUUGAGUUGCCUGAAGAAUUUCCACAGUUCCCCAAUAAAGUGGAUUUUAUCCAAGAACUCUCUGAGGUUCUUGUUCAAUUUGGGAUCCCUCCUGAGGGCAGCCUACAUUGCAGUGAGAGUACCAGCAAACUGAAGAAUAUGGUUCUGAAAGACUUGGUCAAUGACAAAAAGAACGGCAAUGUCUGUACUAAUAACAUCAGCAUGUAUGAGUUACUGAAGGGCAAUGAAACCAUAGCCCGCUUGCAGGCUCUGGCCAAGCGUACUGGUGUGGCUGUGGAAAAAAUGGACCUCUCUGCUUCUCUGGGUGAAAAAGACAAGGAUUUAAAACUGCAUUGUGAAGAGGCAGAACUAAGGGACUACCAGCUCAAUGUACAGCUCCGAGAGGUCUUUGCUAACCGUUUUACACAGAUGUUUGCAGAUUACGAAGCAUUUGUCAUUCAGACUGCCCAGGACAUGGAAUCCUGGCUGACCAACCGGGAACAGAUGCAGAACUUUGACAAAGCUUCCUUUCUGUCUGACCAGCCUGAGCCUUACCUGCCAUUUCUUUCACGCUUCAUUGAAACACAGAUGUUUGCCACCUUUAUUGAUAAUAAAAUUAUGUCUCAGUGGGAAGAGAAAGAUCCUUUGCUUCGGGUCUUUGACACUCGGAUUGAUAAGAUAAGGCUGUAUAAUGUAAGGGCACCCACCUUGCGGACAUCUAUAUAUCAGAAAUGCAGCACUUUAAAAGAAGCAGCCCAAUCAAUUGAGCAGAGACUGAUGAAAAUGGAUCACACUGCAAUCCACCCACAUCUACUUGAUAUGAAAAUUGGUCAAGGCAAAUAUGAGCAGGGGUUCUUUCCAAAGUUACAGUCCGAUGUCUUGGCAACAGGACCAACCAGUAACAAUCGCUGGGUAAGUCGGAGUGCCACUGCACAGCGCAGGAAAGAACGCCUUCGCCAGCAUUCUGAGCAUGUUGGGCUGGACAACGACUUGAGGGAGCCUUCCGGGGAACUUUUGGUCUGUCAGAACUCCAUGGCAUUCUGGGAGUGGGACCAGGGUCCACCUCCUCCUGCACGACUUCCUAAAAAAUCCUUCUCUGAGUGCUGCCUGAAAUAUAUGCAAGAGGCACGAAGUUUAGGAAAAAACCUGAGGCAACCCAAACUGUCAGACCUCUCUCCUGCAGUUAUUGCACAGACCAACUGUAAAUUCGUAGAAGGCUUAUUAAAAGAAUGUAGAAUGAAGACAAAGCGCAUGUUGGUGGAGAAGAUGGGACAUGAAGCGGUGGAACUUGGCCAUGGAGAAGCAAACAUCACCGGCCUGGAGGAGAACACCUUGAUCGCCAGCCUUUGUGACCUGCUGGAGAGGAUAUGGAGCCAUGGCUUGCAGGUCAAGCAGGGGAAGUCGGCUUUGUGGUCACAUUUAAUUCAAUUUCAGGACAGAGAAGAGAAACAAGAGCACCUUGCAGAAUCACCAGUUGCCCUCGGACCAGAAAGAAGAAAAUCUGACUCAGGAGUUAUGUUGCCAACGCUCAGGGUCUCUCUUAUUCAGGACAUGAGGCAUAUUCAAAACAUGAGUGAGAUCAAGACUGAUGUUGGACGAGCUCGGGCGUGGAUAAGACUGUCUCUAGAAAAGAAGCUCUUGUCCCAGCAUCUUAAGCAGUUGCUUUCUAACCAACCACUCACCAAGAAGCUUUAUAAGCGAUAUGCUUUUCUACGUUGCGAAGAAGAAAGAGAGCAGUUUCUUUACCACCUUCUUUCUCUCAAUGCUGUGGACUAUUUCUGCUUCACCAGUGUGUUCACCACUAUCAUGAUUCCGUAUAGGUCAGUGAUCAUCCCAAUCAAAAAGCUGAGCAAUGCAAUAAUCACAUCAAACCCUUGGAUCUGUGUAUCAGGAGAGCUGGGAGACACAGGAGUAAUGCAGAUUCCCAAAAACCUCCUCGAAAUGACCUUUGAGUGCCAGAACUUGGGGAAGCUGACCACUGUUCAGAUUGGUCACGAUAACUCAGGACUGUUAGCCAAAUGGCUAGUGGAUUGUGUCAUGGUCAGAAAUGAAAUCACAGGACAUACAUACAGAUUCCCAUGUGGGCGGUGGCUGGGGAAAGGCAUUGAUGAUGGGAGCCUGGAGAGAAUUCUUAUUGGAGAGUUGAUGACAUCAGCAUCAGAUGAAGAUCUAGUAAAGCAGUGUCGGACUCCACCCCAGCAGAAGUCACCCACCACGGCUAGGAGAUUGAGCAUCACUUCACUGACAGGAAAAAACAACAAACCCAAUGCUGGGCAGAUACAAGAAGGAAUUGGAGAAGCUGUGAACAAUAUUGUGAAACAUUUUCAUAAACCUGAAAAAGAGAGAGGAAGCCUCACCGUGUUGCUGUGUGGAGAAAAUGGCCUGGUUGCAGCCCUUGAGCAAGUUUUCCACCAUGGGUUCAAAUCUGCCCGCAUCUUUCACAAGAAUGUCUUCAUCUGGGACUUCAUAGAGAAAGUGGUUGCUUAUUUUGAAACAACUGACCAGAUUCUAGAUAAUGAAGAUGAUGUCCUUAUUCAGAAAUCAUCCUGCAAAACCUUCUGCCACUACGUAAAUGCUAUUAAUACUGCACCCAGGAACAUUGGGAAGGAUGGCAAAUUCCAGAUUUUAGUUUGCCUUGGAACAAGGGAUCGCCUGCUCCCACAGUGGAUUCCAUUGUUAGCUGAGUGUCCUGCCAUCACUCGAAUGUAUGAAGAGAGCGCUCUCCUGCGAGACCGCAUGACUGUCAACUCCCUUAUCCGAAUUCUGCAGACCAUUCAGGACUUCACCAUAGUCCUAGAAGGAUCACUCAUCAAAGGAGUGGAUGUGUAACCCAACUGGCUAGAAACUCUCAGUCCAAACCUUGCUCCUUCCCCAACUAGGGGACCGAUUUGGACUUGUCUGACAGUAGUGAGUCACUGCAGGGGCAGCCAAACAUAUGCCCCAUUUGGAACAAUCCUCACUCUACAGACAAGGCAAAAUGUUGUAUUGUAGUUCAUUUGAACCUGGAAUUUAGUAUAAAAUAGAGUAUUUUCAUGUGUUAGAUGUGUGUAAAUAUGCUAUCUUCUUUAAGAAAUUAUAUUACUCUAAUAAGAUGCUUUUCUUAGAUUGAAUAUUCCUGUGACUUAAAAUAAGUAGCUUAAAAAUGUUGGGGGUUGGGGGGAAGAGUGGUGCUAGCCAGGAAGAAGCCAGUAAACAUGUAAAUAUAGUGCAACCCAGUCGGGCUUUUUUUUUUCUCCAGGUAUCACAAAGAAACCCAGAAUGCAUUGUUAUGUAGUAGCCAUCCAUCUUGGAGUCUGAUCCUUUGUAUUGUGGAUGCACACAGCUUUACCUACUGUACUGGUAGUCUUCACUUCUAUCUUUUAAGUUACAAACUGUUUUAUAUAUUUGAAUCGCUAGUCACUUUUCCAGUCUUUUGGAAAAAAAUUUCAGUCCGCACAAGAUGAUAUAAUUGGAGUAUUUUAAACACUAGACCCCAGGAGCUUGGCUGAACUGGAAAGAGAACAUACAAAGCUCUGAGAAAUGUGUUCAAUUGUGGGAUUAUAACUUCUUUACACUUCGGAAAGAUUAGCCUAGACUAACUUCAUUCUUGGCAUUUUUAUUCUUGUUAUUUGAGGUACUUUGGGAAGAUGUGAAUUUCAGUGUUAGAUUCAUAGUGAUAAGAACUGCAAACAGCAAUUUGAUUCUGUACUUUUAAUUUGGCCAUCUAAACUGUGCAGUGGUCUACCUCUUAAGGAUAACCAUGAGCCCUGUCUUUGUUAGGGUCUAAUCACCCACCUCUCCAGGGCCCAUCCCCCCUCGGGAAAUGGAAGGAAUGUCUAAGGAGGAGGAGGGCUGUGUGUGGCUUGGAAUGUUUUUGUGAAAGCAUUUGUUGACCAUGAUAAUGCAAAUAACAGAAGGAGAGAGAGAAUGAACCCUUUCUGGGUGUUUCAGGGCAAGCUUUACGUUCCUUUGUAGGAAGGGGAGUAAUAAUGUAAAACAACUGACCCAGAGAAGCUAAAAGCCACUGGCAGCACAGGCUGACAAAAUGGAAGCAAAGCAAGAGGUGGCAACAAUUUUGAAAGACCAAAAGUUGUGAGUAACUUUCCAGUUUGAUAGUUUAUAAAGAAGUUAAGUAAAUGUAGUAUUGGCUAGUUACUGUAAGUCCUCAUCUUCUGGUAGGUCCUGUAACUCUAAUUAGGCAUUUGUACAUUUUUAGCAGCAAAAUUGCCUCAGCAGAGCUCCCAGUUUUAUUCCCAGUUGUGGCUGAAAAGCAAAGCCAUGGCAUCAGUAUCCUUGUGCAAUCGGAGGUUGCUGGGCUUUCACCACCUGUGUUGUUAACCUUAUUUCCUGGAGGAAGAAACAGAUGAAACAAGUGCCUAACUCCCUUUAUCAAACACAGCCAAGGACAGCCUCUUUUAACAUGUGACUUCAUACUUGAGGAAAAGGAGAGUUGACAGCUGUAUUUAAAAACCCAUGGAGCCGGGUGCGGUGGCUCACGCCUAUGAUCCCAGCACUUUGGGAGGCCGAGGCAGGCGGAUCACAAGGUCAGGAGAUUGAGACCCUCCUGGCUAACACCGUGAAACCCCGUCUCUACUAAAAAUACAAAAAAUUAGCCGGGCGUGGUGGCGGGUGCCUGUACAGGAGGCUGAGGCAGGAGAAUGGCGUGAACCCGCGAGGCGGAGCUUGCAGUAAGCUGAGAUCGCGCCACUGCCCUCCAGCCUGGGCAACAGAGCAAGACUCCAUCUCAAAAAAUAAAUAGAUAAAAAUAAAAACCCAUGGAAAUGGUUUAAGAAAAUGGUUCUGGGUACACCAGAAAUUUGUUUGCCUGAAGCUAAAGUGUGUCUACAAUGGUACAGCUCUUCCAGGGACAUGGGAAGUUUAUCGUGGGAGAUAUCCAGAACCUGUUUUACACUGGGCUCCUACUGUGUUUGGUGAUCAGAAACUAUAGAGGGGUCCAACCCAGGAUUUCAUGUUUGUAUCUUCAUAAGGCCAUGCUCCUGACAGGUCUAGGCAACCUGGGGGAUGACUUAGGUUAAUGUGCUAGGAUUGACACACCUCAUCCAGCCUUCUUACUUUGUGGAUGGGAACACUUAAGGAAUAGAGAGAUUAAAUCUUACACUUACCCCACAGCUGGUUACUGACAACACAAGCUCUAGAAUUCAUGUUUGUUUGUUUGUUUUAUUUCACCAGGCUGCAUGAGACUGACCUUCCGGCAUUCUUACUAAUAGUCUUUCUAUUAUACUAUUGGAUCUUUAUUCAUCCACCUAUACAAGUAGGAAAUAAGGAUGAAUAUUCAUUUAGAAGAAUUAAUAUUCAUAUUAACACAUUGCUCUCAGAUUAUUGGGAAUUAACAUCUUGUAAAAACUGGGAGCAGGCCAGGUACGGUGGCUAACGCCUGUAAUCCUGACACUUUGGGAGUCUGAGGCGGGUGGUUCAUCUGAGGUCAGUCGGGAGUUCAAGACCAGACUGGCCAACAUGGUGAAACCCCGUCUCUACUAAAAAAAAAAAAUAGACAAAAAUUAGCGGGGGGGUGGUGGCAGGGCCUGUAAUUCCAGCUACUCAGGAGGCUGAAGCAGGAGAAUCGUUUAAACACAGGAGGUGGAGGUUGCAGUGAGCCGAGAUUGUGCCACUGCACUCCAACCUGGGUGACAAGAGCGAGACUCCGUCUCAAAAAAAAAAAAAGAAAAAAACUGCAGCCAAAGUUGGAUUUGCGGCCUAUGAAUAAAACCAUUACUUUAAAAAGUAAUACCCCCAAAAAAGUUACACCUGAAGUUUCAUCUUCAUGCCUUUGUGUAAUAUUACUAUAAUGGUGAAAUGAUGAUUUAAAAAAAACACAUCAGAACUGACACAUCCUCUUGGAUGAUGGGUCCUUCAGUCACCUUGUGAGCCCAUGUACUUAUUCCGUUGAUACAGCCUGUGCUAUAAACAUGUGGGGCCCUCCUUGUGUGAGCUGCUUGAAUGGCCAGUACCCCCAUUCUUUUGAAUAUUCCCAAUGGCAGUCAAUCUUGGCCUUUAAGAAUAAAUUUAAAUAUUUGGAAAUAGUCCUUAGGAUCCAAGUUUGAUCAAUGAAAAGGAUGCUUAAGCUGAGUUUGGGGUCACAUAAGAAGUGCAGUUAUAAAGAAAUAAGACAUGUUGGGCAUGGCAGUACACACCUGUAGUCCCAGCUGCUUGGGAAGCCAAGGCAGGAGGAUCACUUCAACCCAGGAGUUUGAGUCCAGCCUGGGUAACAUAGGGAAACCCCAUCUCAAAAAAACAAAACAAAGGACUUAGUUUUUAUGUGGCUCAUAAGUGUCUCUAAGUUAUACCAAAAGUUUGAGCACAACAGUAGUAGCAGAAUGCUUAGAAUAAAUGCUUGACUUUUAAGCUGACUUUUGGAAGGACCAUACCCACAUAGAGGCAUCUUUUCUGCUGUGGUAAUUUUUUAAAUUAAUACAUUGCUUUAGGAUUACAUCUCAAAGUAAAUAAAAAAAUCAAUAUUUAAUUUGUUUUUUUCCUGCAAAUAAAUUAAAUGCUGGGACCAUAAUGAUUAUUUUUGCAUAGUAAUAGCUGGUGAAGAAGUUGUUUUAAAAUUAAAUUGCCAAAAGUAUUACCUCUUGAAAAAUUUAUUUUCCCAAAGUUUUUCAUAUGUCAUGAAACCCCUAAUCUUGACCUUUAUGACACAGUGGCAUUACACUGAUGUUGGAAGCAUGUGUGAGAUCUGUGCCCUGGUCGGGAGUCAUAUGCCUUAAAAAUGACUGCGAGUCAGUGUGAAGUAGUAUAAAGUGGAGUCCUACGUGGGAAAAAGCAGGCUACUGAGGACAAAAACCUCCCAACCCUCCCCACCUUGUUUUCCACUGGGAAUGAGAAUUUGAUAUGAGAAACUUCAACCUUGCAGAAGUGUGGAUUUCCCUCUGAAAUUUAAAUGUUUCACACAUUUUUGUACCUUUUGUAACCUUGUGGUAUUUACUUUCACAUGGCUUUUUAAAAAAUUAUUUUAAUGAACUUCUAUCACACUAUAUGAAUGAUAUGGGGGAAAUACUGAACUGCUCAUAUUUCCUUUUUUGGCAAUAAAGCACUGUUAUAUGUAAAUGUAAGUGAAAAAGAGGUUCAAGACUAUACAACAGCUUAUGUGUAGUAUAUGUUGACAUCCCUAAGGUAUUUUGAAACAUGAGGUGACAGACAAGGACCUCAAAUUUCCAGGGAAAUAUUUAUUUCACAACAUUAGGAGUGUAGCUCUUCAUAAUGAAAUAUCUUCUUUCUGCUAAAGAUUACAAUUUUUCAUUUAGGGAACUGUGAAUAUUUUCUGUGAGGUUUACAGAAACUAGUGUAUCCUUUUCACUAUGUUGAAAAGACAAUCUGAACUUUAGCUAUUUAUAUUUCAGUAUUAACACACCUUCACUGAUUGAGAGUCUUGAGCCCUUCUCUACUUUUAUAAAGUGAAUCCUAUUUCCAAGUCAUCCAUGUCUUUUGAAGUCUGUUUCUUAUAUAAGUAUUUAUUACUUUACUGUUUAGCAUAAAUAGGAGACAGAAAAGGAUAAUAAACUACUAGGUCCUUUAUUCCUAUUAAAAUAAAUUUAUAAAUCCCUUGAAUCAACUGAAUUCUAAGCUUUUUGAAGAGGUUGCUGAUGUAGUGUGAUCAAAAGAAUCUAAGGAGAACCUCCUCUCCAAAAUCUGAUUGGAGCUGUUCACCCUCUCAAGGACAAGAUAAAGAUUGACUUCAGAGAUAUAUCACAUCAAGCUAGAGGAAAAAAAAAAAACCUCAAAUAAAAUUUUUCCUCAUUCGAAGGGAUCCAGGGUAUCCUUGGGUUAUGUAGGAGGGAAUCAUAUUUGUUCUAAUUUACCUGAAUGUACUUGUGUGUGAAUCCAAUCUUGAUUCUAAACACCAAAUCUUGUCAACAGUAGAGAAGUAUAGUAAGGAGUUCCUGUUGUCAAUCAAAUGAGGGUGUGAAACAUUUAGAAUGCUCUGUGUUACACUUGAACCAUGUAUAAAUGUAACCUGUGUAUCUUUUUUUUAAUUAGCUUUUCUGAAUUUAAAUUAUAUUGUUUUUCUUUGUAUUGUUAGCAAAAUGCAUCAGAACUGGAUUUUUUUUCUCAUCUGAACAUAAUAUAAAAUUUGAAAGAGUAUUGUGAUAUUAAGCACUUUAACAUACAUAUCAGACAAACUGACGUGGGUUUUUCAGGUUUGGGAGUACAUUUAAAUAUGACUUUUCAUGCUUUGUUCUUUACAAAUAAAACUGUGGGAUUGAUA